GUUUAACACAGAGAGCUUCCUGGAGCCAAGCCUCGAGCUAACUGCUUUAAUGCAUUAACUCACUUAAUUCUCACUGCCAGGAGAGUGGGUACACAUUAUUUCCAUUUCAUAGGCAAGGAAGUGGAGAGGUACGGAGAAGUCAAGUCAUUUGCCCGGGUAGGAAGAGGGGGAGGCAGUGGAAUGGAGACACUUGCUGCCUGGGAAGACUCGAGGUGGCCCCUCCAAGCUGGGGGCGUGGGCGACUUGUUUCCUGUUGGGGGAGGGGGAGAAGAGUACAUUCCUCCCUCCCCGCCCUCCCACAUGUUGGGGGAGAGGCUGGCUGAGAGCAUGUCCCACUCCGGACUAGGGGGAACCCCACUGUCCGUCUCAGCUCCCCAUGAGGCCGUGGAGAAAAUCCCGGCCGCACCACCUGGGUCUCCGCCAUGAACGGGCCUGCCCUGCAGCCCUCCUCGCCCUCUUCCGCGCCCUCAGCCUCCCCGGCGGCGGCCCCGCGGGGCUGGAGCGAGUUCUGUGAGUUGCACGCCGUAGCGGCGGCCCGGGAGCUGGCCCGCCAGUACUGGCUGUUCGCCCGGGAGCAUCCGCAGCACGCGCCGCUGCGCGCCGAGCUGGUGUCGCUGCAGUUCACCGACCUCUUCCAGCGCUACUUCUGCCGCGAGGUGCGCGACGGACGGGCGCCGGGCCGCGACUACCGGGACACAGGCCGUGGGCCCCCAGCCAAGGCCGAGGCGUCCCCGGAGCCAGGCCCCGGCCCCGCCGCCCCUGGCCUGCCCAAGGCCCGCAGCUCUGAGGAGCUGGCCCCGCCGCGGCCGCCCGGGCCCUGCUCCUUCCAGCACUUUCGCCGCAGCCUCCGCCACAUCUUCCGCCGCCGCUCGGCCGGGGAGCUGCCAGCGGCCCACACCGCUGCCGCCCCCGGGACCCCCGGAGAGGCUGCUGAGACCCCCGCCCGGCCUGGCCUGGCCAAGAAGUUCCUGCCCUGGAGCCUGGCCCGGGAGCCGCCACCCGAGGCGCUGAAGGAGGCGGUGCUGCGCUACAGCCUGGCCGACGAGGCCUCCAUGGACAGCGGGGCACGCUGGCAGCGCGGGAGGCUGGCGCUGCGCCGGGCCCCGGGCCCCGAUGGCCCCGACCGCGUGCUGGAGCUCUUCGACCCACCCAAGUGGCCAGAGCCUGAGCUGUCCAGGCUGAGGUUUCGACUGAAGCAGGGGUUGUCCUGCGCCCAUGUGCCCACACGCUGCAACCUGGCUGGAGCCUCUGGCAUAGGACACCCAUACCACCAGAGUUCAAGGCCCAAGCUACAAGCAGCUUGCUCCAGCAUCCAGGAGGUCCGGUGGUGCACACGGCUUGAGAUGCCUGACAACCUUUACACCUUUGUGCUGAAGGUGAAGGACCGGACAGACAUCAUCUUUGAGGUGGGAGACGAGCAGCAGCUGAAUUCAUGGAUGGCUGAGCUCUCGGAGUGCACAGGCCGAGGCAGGCUGGAGAGCACAGAAGCAGAGAUGCAUAUUCCCUCAGCCCUAGAGCCUAGCACGUCCAGCUCCCCAAGGGGCAGCACAGAUUCCCUUAACCAAGGUGCUUCUCCUGGGGGGCUGCUGGACCCGGCCUGCCAGAAGACGGACCAUUUCCUGUCCUGCUACCCCUGGUUCCACGGCCCCAUCUCCAGAGUGAAAGCAGCUCAGCUGGUUCAGCUGCAGGGCCCUGAUGCUCAUGGAGUGUUCCUGGUGCGGCAGAGCGAGACGCGGCGUGGGGAAUACGUGCUCACUUUCAACUUUCAGGGGAUAGCCAAGCACCUGCGCCUGUCGCUGACAGAGCGGGGCCAGUGCCGUGUGCAGCACCUCCACUUUCCCUCGGUCGUGGACAUGCUCCACCACUUCCAGCGCUCGCCCAUCCCACUCGAGUGCGGCGCCGCCUGUGAUGUCCGGCUCUCCAGCUACGUGGUAGUCGUCUCCCAACCACCAGGUUCCUGCAACACGGUCCUCUUCCCUUUCUCCCUUCCUCACUGGGAUUCAGAGUCCCUUCCUCACUGGGGUUCAGAGUUGGGCCUUCCCCACCUUAGUUCUUCUGGCUGUCCCCGGGGGCUCAGCCCAGAGGGUCUCCCAGGGCGAUCCUCACCCCCCGAGCAGAUCUUCCACCUGGUGCCUUCGCCCGAAGAACUGGCCAACAGCCUGCAGCACCUGGAGCAUGAGCCUGUGAAUCGAGCCCGGGACUCGGACUACGAAAUGGACUCAUCCUCCCGGAGCCACCUGCGGGCCAUAGACAAUCAGUACACACCUCUCUGACCAGUGAGGAAUUCCAGGCCUCAACAGCUGCCCUUGAGGAGCACAGGCAGAAGUGUGAACUUGUGAAUGUAAUUGAUCUUUCCUUCCUUCCAGAGAAAGAUUUAAGGGACACUGUUAACUGCUCGUGCCAGUUUGGAAGUGACCCUUCUAUUAGGCCUGUUGAAGGGCCCUCCUGUAGGUUUCAUCUAUCCACCUGGCUUUCUCCUUAUUGUUUACAGAUGUAGUUCUUGUUAGAGGAUGCCGCUAGCUCCUGCCCGGGGUCCCUAUGCCCAGUCCCCGUUACUCUUAGAGAAAGGAGUUGGGGUGAGGGCCAGAGCUGGCAGUGGAAACUUGUUCUCUUUUUCACUGACACUGUCACAGCGGAUGACAGACUUUCUACGGGGAGGAGGGGGGGAUCAUCAGGAAGCCCAGAACACUAACAAGCGGUUCUCCCAUCUACCGUCAGUCCACAUGGCAGGUCUGCUGUGUCCACACCACAGAUGACCACAUCUAAUCCUGCUUCUACUCUCAGCUUUAGGACAAAAGCUCUGUCAGAGGCACAAGCUGAAGGUCAAAAAUGAUUUAAAACAUUUUACCUCAGACUAAUUUCUUUAAAGGAUUCAGGUUCAAAACUUAACCACUGCUUAUUUCAGUGCACUGUUUCAACUAACACCCAUGCUAUUUUUGUAGUCAGAAACAGCUAUGCAAACCCUACCUAAUUUACAGUCUGAGCCAGCAUGCUGGCUUGUCUACUGCAUCCUCGGGACAGUCACCUGCCACUGAGUGGCCACUGUCCUUCCUAAAUGUCAAGAAGUGAAGUAUGUCACCCUUUCAGGGAAAUUCAGGCAAUUACUGAAAUAGGAGGGUGGCAAGAACAGUUCUAUCCUGGUGCCUUACGAAUAAAAAACUGGAUUCUGGUUUACAGCAGCUUUACAGUGAUAGUUAAAUUAACUGGGGCUAGGGGAAGAGCAAGCAAAAAGGGAAGAAGGACUCCUAGGCCCUUUCUAGUAAAUCCUUCAGCAACAAGGCUGGCUUGGUGCCCUCCAAGCAUCUAAUGGCUUAUUAAAUUAUCCCACAAGUGGGUUUUAGGCUCCUUUUUUGAGCCAAAAUGGAAGCUGGGAAUCUGGUGCCAUAACUAAUGAGAAACUCCUUUAAUAGCCCACAAUCAGUGUUCUGUUCUAGCUGGCUACUGCUUCACUGGAUUGAGAAUCUAUCUAUCUCCUUGCACACAUGGGCACACACAAUCUCCACCAUCCAGGGAGGUCCUGAAGUCAAAUCUCUAUCUAUACAAGUGAUACAAUUCAUAGGGGGCUGGCUCCUCCCAGAACCUGUCUGGAGGCUCAGAAACGGGGGCAGUGACAGUGGAGUCAGCUGCUCUUGGGUGCCAGCAGAGCCAUUCAGUACAACCCCCAGGCUCACAGCAGUGGCUUCUAGGAAACUGGGAGUUUAGAUCAGCUUUACAGAUACAUCGAUCAGAGGCUAAAAUGAAACCUCAGCCUAAAACUCAUAGGACUGACUGCCUGGGAGGAGGGUUAGGUCUGCUUCUUCCACUUAUACUUAGUCUCUGUGCUCCAAGAGGUCAAAUUUUUGCUUCUAGAAUUUCCUUGGGGUCUUUCAGAGGGUGGGGGAACAAACCCCUAUGCACUUUUCUUUUUUUUUUUUUUGAGAUGGAGUUUCUCUUGUCAACCGGGCUGGAGUGCAGUGGUGCAAUCUUGGCUCACUGCAACCUCCACCUUCCUGGUUCAAGCGAUUCUGCCUCGACCUCUCAAGUAGCUGGGAUUACAAGCACCAGCCACCAUGCCUGGCUAAUUUUGUAUUUUUAGUAGAGACAGGGUUUCACCAUGUUGGCCAGGCUGGUCUCGAAUGUCUGACCUCAGGUGAUCCACCCGCCUUGGCCUCCCAAAGUGCUGGGAUUACAGGCGCGAGCCACCGCGCCCAGCCUACACCACUUUUAGUACCAACACUCUUGGGUGAUUUCAUGGACCCUAAAGCAGACCUGACACUGAUCCAGAUUUGCAGUCCAUUUUUAAGGACACCUGUCUUUAUUUCCUCAAAGUCAAGCAGCUUUCUCUGGAAAAUGAAUGCUAAUUAGUGUGAACCAAAAGAGUAAGUAAGAGUCUGAAGUUUUUUUAAAGGAGAAAGCUUAUUAUGGAAAGUCACUGGUCCUCCCCUCCGCACAGGAAAGGUACCCAGUAGAUAAUGAACCAAAUUAAGUUCCCUCCCUCCAGCCAGAAGUUAAACAUCUGGGAUAUGACGUCUUCAUGCCAGGGGCACUCAUUUCUUAGCAGCCUCUCUACAUACAUCUCUCAGGUGGUGCCAAGAGGCACACCAGGUAGAGCAAACUUAGCAGCUCUGACUAACAGGCUGCAAAGUGCAAGUUCAGAUUCUGUGGCAGAGAUUUGGAAGGCACCCACCUCCAGACUGCUUCCCGUCCAAGUUACCAGGACAGCUCAAAAACAUGCUGACAGAAAACUCCCAUGGCUCUAGGAAGAAGUGACACUAAGCCAACACCUUUCUUUAUGUGGGAGCAGAAUCAGCUGAUGAAGGGGUGGGCAGCAGUGUGGGGCAGGCACCCCACUGGCUGCAGCUAGCCCACCAUAGGCACAGCACAUCCCACCACUCUCCUUCCAGUCCUGACCAGGCCCCAGCCGGCAACUUCUACCGAGAGCCAUGGCUCAACACCAAACUGGACAGUAGACAUCAUGAUCCCUCCAGUUAGCUCUAAUUACAGACCCCACCAGUACAGCUUGACAGCUCCCGGCACCAUCCCUUCCUUCAUCUGACUUAUUGAACUUUUACAAACUAACAGUCACCAGCACCAAAGAAUUAAGUCAACUAACCUGCCUUGAAUUUUAGACCAGCAAUCCAUAUGGCUUUAUCUGGUAUAAAUCUUCUGCCUUUGAUCAUUUCUGGACCGUAGGAAAAAGGAAUAGCAAUCAUUAAAAUCUUGGGCCAGAGAACACUAUUUUUACAUAACAGUUUCUUAACCUAAAGUCAAGGCCUUGGACUCUUCCCUGAGGGUUGCCUGAGAUUCCUUCAUGCUUUCUAUUCAGGACUAAGUCCCUUACUGCAAAUGUGUUAGCUCUAACAUCUCCCACAAGCUAGAGGAACUUGCGAGUAUAUUAACAAGGACACAUCUGACAUCCUGUGUUUGGUUAGAAUAUACAGCACAUUGUGAUAACAUAAAGUGGAUUCAUCUUGUAUCAUUAUAGGCAGAAGGUAUUUGGCAAAUUUUUAUGUAUUGUUUUAUGUACUGUACAAGUAACUUAUUCUUGAAUAAUGCAAAUUUUGCUAUAAUGUACAAAUUGCUAUAUGUGAAUUAAAAAGUUUUCAGAAUCUUGA